AGUUGGCGCCCAUGGAGCCAGAGCUGCUGGUUCGGAAGGUGUCUGCAUUGCAGGUGCGGGGGCGGGCGCGGGGUUCACAGGAUUUUUCCUUUAGGGAAAUCAUGGGGUCUCGUACCUGGACCUCCCAGCGAGAUGCUACCACGUUCAGUCCCCUAACUGCGCGCCAACCUCUGGAGAUACCGGCUGUCCCCAACCGCGCUGAGGAAAGCUGGGACCCACGGACUCCCUGCCCUGCGCGUCCCCACUCCCACCACACGCUCGCGCCGGAUCAGGGAAACGGGAAGAGCCUUAAGGCCUGCGUCCGGGGCUUCUUGGUCCGACGCCAGUUCCAGAGCCUGCGAGCUGAGUAUGAGGCGAUUGUACGAGAGGUCGAGGGCGACCUGGGCACGCUUCAGUGGACCGAGGGCCGCAUUCCCAGGCCGCGAUUCCUCCCAGAGAAGGCAAAAUCCCAUCAGACCUGGAAAGCAGGAGACAGGGUAGCAAAUCCAGAGCAGGGGCUGUGGAACCACUUCCCAUGUGAAGAGUCUGAGGGAGAGGCCACCUGGGAGGAGAUGGUGCUGAAGAAGUCAGGAGAGAGCUCAGCAAAUCAAGGAAGCCUCUGCAGAGAUCACAGCUCCUGGCUUCAGAUGAAGCAGAACAGGAAACCCAGCCAAGAGAAGACCAGAGACACGACAAGGAUGGAGAAUCCAGAAGCCACAGAUCAAAGACUGCCCCACAGCCAACCUCAGCUUCAAGAGCUUCAGUACCACCGCAGCCACUUGGCCAUGGAAUUGCUGUGGCUGCAACAGGCCAUCAAUAGCCGUAAGGAGUACCUACUUCUUAAACAAACACUGAGAUCCCCAGAGGCGGGCCCGAUCAGAGAGGAACCCCGCGUGUUCCUAGAACAUGGGGAACAGGCCUGUGAGAGGGACCAGUCACAACCAAGCGCACCACUGGAGGACCAGUCCUACAGAGACAGGACCACUGGAGAGCUAGAACAGGAGGAUGACUCCUGUCACAGGGUCAAAUCACCCCACAGAUCCCCAGGAAGUUUGGCCACUACACAAAAAAACAUUGCUGGGGCUAAGUGCAGAGAACCAUGCUACAGCAAGUCUGGACCACCGUCGUCUAUACCAUCAAACAGCCAGGCCUUGGGGGACAGGCUCACCAAAGGGCCAGACGAUGGAAGACAGACCUUUGGAGGGACCUGCCUGCUGCAGAUGAAAAUCCUGGAGGACCAGACCCCCAGAGGUUUAAAACCUAGGAACCAUUGUCCCAGGAAGUCCAGGACACAGCUGUCUGCACUCUAUGAGGACUCAAAUAUUAAGGAGAUGUCUCCCAGAAAACUAGACCACAAAGAGCCUGACUGCCGAACAGUCAGGACACAAGAGUUGGGCCUCUCAGAGGACCACAUCAUCUGGGAUGGUACCUUGGGGGGGCCAGAGCAUAGUGUCCUCGAUCUCUGGAGGACUAAACCACCCAAAGGCCAGGCCCCCACUGAUAGAAGCUCCAGAGAUGGAACCUCCAAUGAGCCUAGUCAUGAAGGACAGAAAAAGCAGAGGACUAUACCAUGGAGAUCAAAGUCACCUGAGAUUCUGUCUUCUACAAAGGCAGGCUGUACAGGAGAGGAACAGUGGAGGGGCAGGCCAUGGAAAACAGAACCACCUGGCUAGACCCUAGGAAGCCAGGAGAGGAUCAGGUUCCAAAGGGGAAUGCUAUGAAAGGGCAGUGAGACAAGACCUCAUCCUACCUCCCUGACCAGCUCUGGCUUCUGCUCCUGCCCCUGGCCAUUGGUGACUAGUGGGGCCAAGAGAAGCUGGAGCAGAGAGCUGGCAUGAGUAUAGGGAAGGAGGAAGGACACAUUUUCAAUCCUCUGCCUGUAGCUCAAUCCAAAUUUGUGGAUAAGGGGCCGGGUGCAGUGGCUCACACCUGUAAUCCCAGCACUUUGGGAGGCCAAGGUGAGUGGAUCACCUGAGGUCAGAAGUUUGAGACCAGCCUGACCAACAUGGUGAAAUGAAACCCCAUCUCAACUAAAAAUAUAAAAAUUAGCCAGGCGUGGUGGUGCAUGCCUGUAGUCCCAGUUACUCGGGAGGCUGAGACAGGAGAAUCGCUUGAACCCAGGAGAUGGAGAUUGCAGUAGGCCAAGAUGAUGCCACUGCACUCCAGCCUGGGCUACAGAGCGAGACACGGUCUCAAAAAACAAAUGUGUGGCUAAGGAGUUACCUGGGGGAAGUAGAAUGAGAGGUCUGUUGGGAAUAAAGGUUUUUCUUAGA